ACACUCACACAGAGACCUCUCUGGGUUUCUUUGCCUUGAGUCUCCCGGGGCUGUGAGAAGCCAGGCGCAUCUCAAACCGAGCUGGCAGCUCCAGGCUCCGGAGCCAUGCCCUGCACGGACCCUCGUCUUUACCACGCUCCUGAGGAAUGAAAGGAACCCAGGGACCCUCAGAAGGCAGCAGUGAUGCGGACCAACCCCCCGGAGCCUGCACCCUUCCGAGGGCCAUAGGCGACCCAGGGAACUGGAGAGAGCUCCAGAAAGGAAAUCCCAGCUUUCCCAAAGUCCCUGUGGAUGCUGACAAAAGGAGACCUGAAUUUUUGGAAGAGCCUGUACUAGGUUACCCGGCUGCAGAGUGAUUUUCCCCUCCGGCACUGACUCUCCCCCUCCAACCCCCAGCCGUCCAGAGUACCAUGAAGAAUUAUGAGGAUGUGUGACAGAGGUAUCCAGAUGUUGAUCACCACUGUAGGAGCCUUUGCCGCUUUUAGUUUAAUGACCAUUGCAGUGGGCACGGACUACUGGUUAUAUUCCAGAGGUGUGUGCAGGACUAAAUCUACAAGUGAUAAUGAAACCAGCAGGAAGAAUGAAGAAGUAAUGACCCAUUCGGGGCUGUGGAGGACCUGCUGCCUAGAAGGGGCUUUCCGAGGCGUGUGCAAGAAAAUCGAUCACUUCCCUGAAGAUGCUGACUACGAACAGGACACAGCCGAAUAUCUCCUGCGAGCUGUGAGGGCCUCCAGUGUCUUCCCCAUCCUCAGUGUCACGCUGCUGUUCUUCGGCGGGCUCUGCGUGGCAGCCAGUGAGUUCCACCGCAGCAGACACAACGUCAUUCUCAGCGCGGGCAUCUUUUUUGUCUCUGCAGGGUUAAGCAACAUCAUUGGCAUCAUAGUUUAUAUAUCAGCCAACGCCGGAGACCCCGGGCAGCGUGACUCCAAAAAAAGUUACUCCUAUGGUUGGUCCUUUUAUUUCGGAGCCUUCUCUUUCAUCAUCGCAGAAAUUGUAGGAGUGGUUGCCGUGCACAUCUAUAUUGAAAAACAUCAGCAGUUACGAGCCAAAUCCCACUCGGAGUUCCUGAAGAAAUCUACUUUUGCCCGCCUCCCACCCUACAGGUAUCGAUUCCGGAGGCGGUCAAGUUCUCGCUCCACCGAGCCCAGAUCCCGAGACCUGUCCCCCAUCAGCAAAGGCUUCCACACCAUCCCUUCCACUGACAUCUCGAUGUUCACCCUCUCCCGGGACCCCUCAAAGAUCACCAUGGGGACCCUCCUCAACUCCGACCGGGACCACGCUUUUCUACAGUUCCACAAUUCCACACCCAAAGAGUUCAAAGAGUCACUGCAUAAUAAUCCGGCCAACAGGCGCACCACGCCCGUCUGAACUGACCUCUGACCUCUGCCCCACGCCCAGCACAGCCUUGGGGGAAGUGUACAGAGAUGUCUCUGAGGUUGCAUGGCAUGGUCCUUGUGAUGGUAUUACUUUUUACAAAGAAUGAAACCAAAUGGACUCAGCCCUCUCCCACAUUUUCCCCUCACCCUCCAAGUCCUAACCCCUCCAUCCUCUCUAACUUUUCAAGCCAAUCCCUUAAUGUCAUUCCUCUCUCUGUGUAUCUGUGCCAGAUGUUUUCCUUUCUUCCUUCUUUACUGGAAGGACCUCCACAUUCUUCCCUCCUUGGAAGAGGACUUUACUAAAAGUCACAGGUGGUGGCCAGGGGGGAUUUCCGAAUCUCCAUCAGGCGCGCUCAUAGUUGUCCCCAUUGUCUACCCACACAAAUCCUCAGGAAACCAACCACCGCCCAGGUGGCCCUGAGGGAGGCAUUCACCUUUAUGUGUUAGAAAAACAUGACCAGAAAUCAAAGAUGUCAGAGCCCCGAAGCAGCUAAUGUAAUAAGCACUCAUGUUAUUAAAGGUUUUGCCUUGUCGUAACCAA